GCCCGUCUCCGCAAGGCCAUCGGUCCGUCCGCCCGCCCUCCCGGCGCUCCUCGCCCCGGCCCCGCUACUCCGGCAGCGCGCGUCGCUUCCUCCGUUCCGGCCGCCGCUAGCCCGUCCCCCGCCCCCGGUCCGGCCGCAGCCGCUACGCGAGGCCGGGGAUUGGCAGCGCGCGUAGGCCGCGCCGCCGCGGAUGGAGCCGGAAUAAAGGGGCGGCCGAGAGAGCAGCUGGUCGCCGCUCGCCCCGCGCCUGCCCUGCAGGCGGCCUGGAGCAGGUGAGCGGCGGGGCGCCCGGGGCCGCAUCUGGGGGCCACCCCCGCGCCCGCCGCACCCCUUCCUCUGCCGGCCCGGCCGCCCCCCCGCGCCCCUCCGCCGCGACCUAGCGGCCUCUUGAGCUUCUGGGCGGCCCAGGCCGGGCCUCGAGGCGCAGCCGCUUCCUGGGCCCGGCCUGUAGCCCUGGGGCCUUUCUCCAGCCCGGCCGCCCUCGGGGCUCGCCCUCGGGUCGCAGCGGCCGGGCCAUCCCGGACGAGGGCUGACAGGACGCAGCCCAGCUGGGCCUGCAGGCAGGGCCGGCGGGAGGUGAUCGGCUUUCAUUCGGUUUCUCAGGGAGGAAGAAGAGACGGGGUGGGGCGCAGGUGGGGGGCCUCCCCUGCCUCUCCUUGCCUCCUCUCUCCCCUUUGCGGAGUGAUCACAGAGGCUUCCUGGCUGCACCUUGCUGCAGGAGGGCCAGGGUGGGCAGGGGGUGCUGCAGACCAAGCCAGGGGACACUGUCUGACAGCCAUUCAUGCCAGAAAAAGCAAACAAAACAGUGGGUUGGCACAGCGGACCUACAGGCGCUCAGAGAAGCCCACCUUCCCCCUCUCUGUCCCGAGAAGGCUUAGAGUGGUACCUGCUUGCUCAAGCAACCUGCUGCCUCCACCCAGAGCAGCCGCUCCUCUCCUCCCUCCCUUCCGGAAGAUGCUGAGGAUGACAGCUUUUAGCCUGACUCUUACAUUUCUUUGGCAGAGCAGUUAGAGGCCAGACUGUCCUGUGAAGGCUUCUCCUUCCUUCUUCCUCUGCUCAGGAGAAAACUUACAAACUUUUAAAUGUAAGAGGCAGAUGAGCUGGGAACCUGGAAGUGGGUUGCAUCUGACUCUGAAAGUUCCUCCCUCUCGCUGGCAUUACCUCAUGCUGCCACAAAGUGAACGGAUCACUGGGGAAGGCAGAGUCUCCCCGGCACUGCUGGGACCCUCCCUUGAAGAGCCCCCAUGUCCUGUAGGCAGAGCCUUGUAGUCUGUCCGCUUGGUUACUGACUCGGGCUGUCUGACCAGCCCCUCUUCUGUGCCUUGUCUGAGGUCCUUGUCCAUCUCUGUGAUUGGGCAGCUUCUCUCUCUGGAUUGGGUCACGUGAAGCGGGAAACUGAAGCCAUUACUCUCCAAACCCUGUUUCAUCUUCCCAAGCAUGUCGGAAAGCUGGCAACAGCCGCCACAGACGCAGCCGCAGCAGCCACAGCCACCGCAGCCUCAGCACCAUGCAGAGCCACCGCCAGCCCUGGCAGAGCACACGCUGCCUCCGGGCACGGCGGAGAACCCCCUGGGCUGUGCCGUCUAUGGCAUCCUCCUGCAGCCAGACCCCGGCCUGCAGCCCCCACAACACGCACCCCUGCAGGCAGCAGGAGAGCCAGGCCCCAAAUGUGGCGUGUGUGGUCACGACCUGGCGCACCUGUCCAGUCCGCAUGAGCACCAGUGUCUGGCGGGCCAUGACCGCUCAUUCCAGUGCACACAGUGUCUCAAGAUCUUCCACCAGGCCACUGACCUGCUGGAGCACCAGUGCGUGCAGGCUGAGCAGAAGCCCUUCGUCUGUGGGGUCUGCAAGAUGGGCUUCUCACUACUCACCUCACUGGCACAGCACCACAGCUCCCACAGUGGCCUGGUGAAGUGUUCCAUCUGUGAAAAGACCUACAAGCCAGCUGAGGCAGCGGAGCCAGCCACCACAGCCGCCCCGUCGCUUCCCGCAGCACCCGCGCCUUCCACUGUCACCCCUGCUGAACAGGCCGACAAGCCCUACAGCUGCCCCAUCUGCCAAAAGCCCUUCAAGCACCUGUCGGAGCUCUCUCGGCAUGAGCGGAUCCACACCGGUGAGAAGCCCUACAAGUGCACGCUGUGUGACAAAAGCUUCAGCCAGUCGUCGCACCUGGUGCACCACAAGCGCACGCACAGCUCCGAGCGGCCCUACAAGUGCGCAGUCUGCGAGAAGACCUUCAAGCACCGCUCUCACCUGGUGCGCCACAUGUACGCGCACUCGGGCGAGCACCACCUGUUCCGCUGCAACGUGUGCGAGUUGCAUUUCAAGGAGUCGUCGGAGCUGCUGCAGCACCCGUGCACGCCAAGUGGGGAGCGGCCCUUCCGCUGCGGCGAGUGCCAGAAGGCCUUCAAGCGGCCCUCGGACCUGCGGCAGCAUGAGCGCACACACAGCGCCGAGCGGCCCUUCAAGUGCGACCUGUGCCCCAUGGGCUUCAAGCAGCAGUACGCACUGAUGCGCCACCGGCGCACACACAAGACCGAGGAGCCCUUCAAAUGCGGCCUAUGUGAGAAGGGCUUUGGGCAGCCCAGCCACCUGCUCUACCACCAGCACGUGCACACCCUCGAGACUCUCUUCAAGUGCCCCGUGUGCCAGAAAGGCUUUGACCAAUCUGCCGAGCUGCUGCGGCACAAGUGCCUGCCCGGCGCGGCCGAGCGGCCCUUCAAGUGCCCUGUGUGCAACAAGGCCUACAAGCGCGCGUCGGCCCUGCAGAAGCACCAGCUGGCCCACUGUGCGGCGGCAGAGAAGCCCCUGCGCUGCACGCUUUGCGAACGCCGCUUCUUCUCCUCUUCCGAGUUCGUGCAGCACCGCUGCGAUCCGGCCCGCGAGAAGCCACUCAAGUGCCCAGACUGCGAGAAACGCUUCAAGUACGCGUCAGACCUGCAGCGGCACCGGCGGGUACACACAGGCGAGAAGCCCUACAAGUGCCCCAACUGCGACAAGGCCUUCAAGCAGCGGGAGCAUCUCAACAAGCACCAGGGCGUGCACGCCCGCGAGCAGCAGUUCAAGUGUGUAUGGUGCGGGGAGCGCUUCCUAGACGUGGCCUUGUUGCAGGAGCACAGCGCGCAGCACAGUGCCGCCGCCGCGGCAGCGGAGGGCGCCUACCAGGUAGCCGCCUGCCUGCCCUGACUCUGCGGCUGUGGCCCCUACCAGCCUGACCUGAGUCGGCGCCGUGGGCCCAGCAGGCCUCGCGCAGCCUAGCUCCUCACAGCUGCCUUGCACCAAGGGCCCCACCCAGCUCGGUGUUCUGAGACCUCGGGAGUGAGGACGCAGGGGUAUGAGGCAGGGAGAGGGUGUGCCGCUCGUACUCCUGGCACCAGCGGGCAGUGCGGGCGGCCAGAUUGCUGUGGCCCAUCCUGAUUCCACAAACCUCUUUCCCAUGACAAGAUUCACUUUCUUGAGAGCCAUCAGCACCCCCCUUAUUUCCGGGGCACUGGAGCCAGGCUGGAAGUCAAGUGGCUUCUCCCUGCCCUAAGGAGGGUGUGAUGCCAGCCCAACCUUCCCAUAUCUUUCAAGCUAGCAGCCACAUAGGUUAGGAAAGCGGAGGCUCAUGGUGGGGCUGGGGCCCCAGAGGUGGGCUAGGUGUAAGGCAUCAGUUGCCGUGUGGGGGAGAAGGCCAGCUUUAAGACGUAGGCCUGGGGACUGGGAGGGCAGAGGGUGAGUCACAGCCCUCUCCGUCUGCUCUAGCCAGGGGCGACGUGUCCCCAGGUUUCUGGCAGGGGAGAUGUGCAGGGUGGGUCUUGGGGCUGGGUCUGCCUGGAGACCAGUGGGCCCAGGGGGAAGGGGGAAGCUGAGAAGUUCGUGUGACACCCUCAGCCAAGGGACAGUGCCAUCCUUGGGGACAGGAGGAAAAGCAGCCUGUCUCUGCUAAGGGCAAAUCCUCCGGUUUUGGAAGCGCCCCUCCCACCUUUGUAGUGCAGUUCCUAGGUGUGGUGGGGAAUGUGCCGUGCUCUCAGCAGACAGAACUGCUGGUGUGAAAGGCAGGGAUUGUCAGCCCACCUGAGGCUGGGAGGAAGCAGGACCAGGCCUAGGAUCUCCCCAGCAGAUGCAAACAAGUGUCCUCCCCUGAAUUGUGUGAACCAAAGCGUCAGGGGCUUGGGGCACAGCCCCAGUCAGCUCAACCCAGUCCUGCUUCAGAGCCAAGACUAGGCCAGGGUGGGGACCCCCCCAGUACCCUCCCUACAUCAAUGUGGCUGCUGGCCUGGACCCCAGGGGUCUGGUACAGCCAAGAUGUUCUGGACAACAUCCAGCUACUUCAAAGGCCAGAGUGUCCUUUGGGUCCUCCUAGAGUCCCCCUAGGUCUCUGGCUGCCCAUGAGGCUCAUGAAGCAGAGGGUAUCCCAGUCAUAGGGAGCAGAAAGAGCAAGUGGGUUAAGGAAGCCUGUGGGGGACCUGGUGGAUGGAGUUGACCAACAUCGCUGGGUGGCUACGGCCCUCCUUAGGAAGCCCAGAAGGACCUUUAUUAUUAAAAUAAUCAUUUUGAACCCUGCUCUAUCCCCUGCCCUCUUCCAGCCCCACCCCUCCCUGGUCUUGAAAGAAGACUAAUCAGUGGGCACACCAAGGGCCCUGAGGGGCAGGGAGAUGCCACCAUGCUUCUCUGUCACCGUAAGAAGGCUGACCAGCCACGCCCACCUCCUCUGUCUGACUGAGUUCCUUCCUGUGGCCACAGGGAGGGGCUGGUCCUUCCCCUCGGUGCUGGCUCUCUGUCACAAUGCCUCAAAAGACAUGGAACCCAGGCCUACAACCGUCCCAACUGCUAAUUCUUUUCCUUUCAUUUUGCUUUCUGAAAGCAGUUUGUUAUACUAUUCAUAACAUUGUAGAGUUUAAUUUCAUGUCAUUUUGGAUCUUAUAUAAAAAUGUGAGGAUUUGGAUUUUUAAAAAGAAUGACUCCAUUUUAGGUAGCCACUUUUGAUGUUAAUAUAUAGUGAGUCCAAUGUAUGCUUUAGAAGUAAAGACAUUGACCGUCACAGA